AGACGUCGAGUGCAGCCCGCCCGGUGCGCGCGGCGUCUUACUGCCAGAUCUCGGAAAUCAGCUGCCAGGGUGGGGCCGCGUUUUGGCGACGGCCACUCGGCCACCCCUGCCGCUCCCGCCUCUCCCAAGAGAUUUUUCUAGCGGGUUAAUUUCCUGUCCGGGUAAACCCUUUGGUGAGUCCCUCGCCCCUCCCUCCCCGCCCCUCCCCUCUCCAUCCCUGCUGUCCCGGCUCCCCAGUCCGUCCGCGCCGCGCUCCAUCGCCCCCGCACGCCCGGGCGCACGCCCUCCCCGCCCGGGCCGCCCUCUGGCUCCCCGCGCCCGGCAGCCAGUGCCUCACCGCGCCGUCCCGCGCCAGGGCUCGCUCCGAGAGCCGCUUCCUUCUCGCCGCGGCCGGCGCGGGCCCCCCGGCCAUGCGCCCCCGAGCCCCAGCCUGCGCCGCCGCGGCGCUCGGGCUCUGCAGCCUUCUGCUGCUGCUCGCGCCCGGGCACGCGUGCCCCGCGGGCUGCGCCUGCACCGACCCGCACACCGUGGACUGCCGCGACCGCGGGCUGCCCAGCGUGCCAGACCCUUUCCCCCUGGACGUGCGCAAGCUGCUGGUGGCCGGCAACCGCAUCCAGCGGAUCCCCGAGGACUUCUUCAUCUUCUACGGCGACCUGGUCUACCUGGACUUCAGGAACAACUCGCUGCGCUCGCUGGAGGAGGGCACGUUCAGCGGCUCGGCCAAGCUCGUGUUCCUCGACCUCAGCUACAACAACUUGACCCAGCUGGGCGCCGGCGCCUUCCGCUCGGCCGGGAGGCUGGUGAAGCUUAGCCUGGCUAACAACAACCUGGUGGGCGUGCACGAGGACGCCUUCGAGACCCUGGAGUCGCUGCAGGUGCUGGAGCUCAACGACAACAACCUGCGCAGCCUCAGCGUGGCCGCCCUGGCCGCGCUGCCCGCGCUGCGCUCCCUGCGUCUGGACGGGAACCCCUGGCUGUGCGACUGUGACUUCGCCCACCUCUUCUCCUGGAUCCAGGAGAACGCAUCCAAACUGCCCAAAGGUUAGAGGCUUCCAGCACUCCUCGGCUCUCAGGCACGUCCCCAUGACCUCUCUGCAUCGGCAUAUCUCUUUCUCCUGCUCUGACCUGCCUGCCUCCCUUUUAUAAGGACCCUUGUGAUUAUAUCAGGACUGCCUGCAAAUCCAGGAUAAUCCCCCCAUCCCAAGAACCUUUAUCUAAUCACAUCGGCAAAGCCCCUUCUGCCUUACAAGGCAGCAUAUUCACAGAUUCUGAGGAUUAGCAUGUGGACGAUUUAGGGGGUCGGCCUGGAUCUCCUCCAGGGAAGUAACCUCACUUCUGUGUCCCCACCUGUGACAGUAGAAGGUCAGAUAAUGGCGAGGUCUUCUCCACCUGUGUAGGCUCAUUUCUCAUGAAACCUCUCCUUGCCCACCCCAAAGGCCCCACCCCGAGGUCACUUCCCCGUACCACAACCCUGGCCCUGGUGACAGCAGUUGCUGCAGCACCGAGCCCCGCUGAAGGCCACCAGGUGCAGAUAUCUGGUGCUGGGAACCUGGGUCUUCCCUGGCCCCUGCUGCUGGAAAAAUUAUAAAUACAAAAAAAAAGCAACUUGAUUUCUGACUUGCCAGGAAAAUCAGAAUUGCUUGUAUUGGUAAAUUAUUUUGAAGCUAUUUGAAGCAUAGAGAGCACUUCGUGAGCCGAGGGUGAGAUGCCUGCACUCACGGGAAGAUAUCCCUGGAAUGACUGUCGCACACAGCACAGAGACAGAAGGGGAGUCCCCAUUCCAGGGAUAGCGUGGCCCCCAGGGAACUCCCAAGAGCGACGGGACUCACGUGGUCGGAGGUUAGGCCUGGGUCAGGGGGGAGAGGGGAGCGGCAGAGCAGAGAUGCGUCACAUCUUUUAUAAUAGAAUCGUGAAUGCUGUGUUAUGUUGGCUUGUCUGCACUUUGAGAUCUGCUGGGUCCACAGAGGUGCCAGUCAAACAGGUCCUGGAUGAGUAAGAGAAGAAUUCAUAGAGUGUCAGGGCUGGGUAAUGGUAUGUUUUCAAAAAGUCCUUUUUUUUUUCUUUUUUGAGGUGGAGUCUCACUCUGUCACCCAGGCUGGAGUGCACUGGUGCGAUCUCAGCUCACUGUAACCUCCAUCUCCCAGAUUCAAGUGAUUCUUGUACCUUAGCCUCCUGAGCAGCUGGGAUUGCAGGCACCCGCCACCAGGCCCGGCUAAUUUUUGUAUUUUUAGUAGACAUGGGGGUUGUGCCAUGUUGGCCAGGCUGGUCUCGAGCUCCUGACCUUAGGUGAUCCACCCACCUCGGCCUCCCAAAGUGCUGGGAUUACAAGCGUAAGCCACCGCACCCGGCCAAAAAUCCUUUUUUUAAGAAUGAAAAUUUUCUCUAUUUUUUGCAUUAUAUUUUUCCUCCAAAUAAAUGUAACAACAACACGUUGUCUA